GGGCGAGGUUGGGCUGCCGUGCUGCUCGGCGGCGCUGAGGUGAGUGUGAGCCCGGCGGGGGCGGGCGCGCGGGGCGCAGACCCUCCCGGCGCAGACCCUCCCCUGCGCGUUGCCCCUGUGCCCGGUCCUCUCGCGGUGCUGCAGGCGUGGGUCCGUCCCGCCAUCAGCGGCACUUCCUGUUCGAGGGACCCCCCGGACAAGGCCCCGAGUACGGACUGCGCCUCGCCGCUCUCUGCCAGCCCUGGGGUCGCUCCUCACGGGGCUCCUUCCGCUCUCGAGCCCCUGACAACUCCCUUGCCCCACGCGGGGUCCCCUGGACUCCUGCCGCACAGAGCGGCUUCUGCGUCCCGAUGCGCUCCAGACCCCUUGGUCCCAGCGGCCCGAGGCUUCCCAUCCCGGCUCCCUCCCACGCUCCUCUCCUGUCAGCUUUUCAGGGGCGGGGCUCGUGCGUCUCGCGGUCCUCCCAGCCCUCUGCGAAUGCCGCCCCUCCUGCCUUUAGCGUCCGCGCUCCGCCAGUGCUCCUCCCUCUGCUUGUGCCUUCCCUCCGCCCCACCCUCCUCGCUUCUGGCGCUCCAAGGCUUUUCUCCCCGCAGCCAGGCAGCCAGAUUUUUGUUUCUCUUCUUUAUUUUUUCUUUCUUUUCUUUUCUCUUCUCUUCCUUCUUUCCUUUCUCUCUCUCUUUUUCUGAGACGGAGUCUCGCUCUGUCGCCCAGGCUGGAGUACGAUGGCGCGAUCUCGGCUCAAUGCACCUUCCGCCUCCCGAGUUCAAGGGAUUCUCCUGUCUCAGCCUCCCGAAUACCUGGGAUUACAGGCGCCCGCCACCAUGCCCAGCUAAUUUUUGUAUUUUUAGUAGAGAUGGGGUUUAACCAUGUUGGCCAGGCUGGUCUCGAACUCCUGACCUCAAGUGAUCUGCCCGCCCCAGCCUCCCAGAGUGCUGGGAAUACAGGCGUGAGCCACUGCGCCCGGCCUCGUUUUCUUAUAUCUCUACAAACCUAAUACUGUUUUUGUCUCUUAAAAAUCUACAUAUGUAUGGCAGAGCACGGUGGCUCACGCCUGCAAUCCCAGCACUUUGGGAGGCCAAGGCGCGGGGGGGAUCACUAGGUCUGGAGAUCGAGACCAUCCUGGCUAACCCAGUGAAACCCCGUCUCUACUAAAAAAUACAAAAAAAUUAGCCGGGCGUGGUAGCGGGCGCCUGUAGUCCCAGCUACUUGGGAGGCUGAGGCAGGAGAAUGACGUCAACUCGGGAGGCGGAGCUUGCAGUGAGCCAAGAUCCCGCCACUGCUCUCCAGCCUGGGUGAUGGAGCAAGACUCCGUCUCAAAAAAAAAAAAAAAAAAAAAAACUACCUAUGUAUUAUACUGUGUAUAUUCUGUACCUGACAGUUUUUCUCAGCCUUAUAACUGUGCUCUAUCUCCUUGACAUUACUUUCCACCACUCUGACUUUGCUGAUGGACGCUGAAGUUUUUUCUUCUUCUACACAGGCACAUGGCCAAAUAGUUGCAUCACAUGUAUCUAAUCCGAGAGUCUCAUGCUUCUGGUAGCUCCUCAGUGACCAGCUCCUGCUCACUGCCCUCAGAAAGCCCAACCCUCAGGCAAUGGCGGCCUUGUUCCUGUCUGCCCCACCCCAGGCCGAGGUGACCUUCGAGGACGUGGCUGUGUACCUCUCCCGGGAGGAAUGGGGCCGCCUGGGCCCUGCUCAGAGGGGCCUCUACAGGGACGUGAUGCUGGAGACCUACGGGAACCUAGUCUCACUGGGAGUAGGACCUGCAGGCCCCAAGCCUGGAGUGAUCUCGCAGUUGGAGCGAGGGGAUGAGCCCUGGGUCCUGGAUGUUCAGGGCACCUCUGGGAAAGAGCACCUGAGAGUCAACAGCCCAGCUCUUGGGACCAGAACUGAGUACAAGGAGUUGACUUCACAGGAGACAUUUGGUGAGGAAGAUCCCCAGGGAUCUGAGCCAGUAGAAGCCUGUGACCACAUCAGUAAGUCAGAGGGGAGCCUGGAAAAGCUAGUGGAGCAGAGAGGCCCCAGGGCAGUCACACUGACCAACGGGGAGAGCAGCAGGGAGUCUGGGGGAAACCUCAGGUUGCUGUCAAGACCUGUUCCUGAUCAGAGACCUCACAAAUGUGAUAUAUGUGAGCAAAGUUUUGAACAGAGAUCAUAUCUCAACAACCAUAAGCGUGUACACAGGUCAAAAAAAACAAAUACAGUUCGUAACUCUGGGGAAAUCUUCAGUGCAAACUUAGUUGUUAAAGAAGAUCAGAAAAUUCCUACUGGGAAAAAAUUGCAUUAUUGCAGUUACUGUGGGAAAACAUUCAGGUACAGUGCCAACCUUGUCAAGCAUCAGCGGCUUCACACUGAAGAGAAGCCCUACAAAUGUGAUGAGUGUGGGAAAGCCUUCAGCCAGAGCUGCGAGUUCAUCAAUCACCGAAGGAUGCACUCAGGAGAGAUUCCCUACCGGUGUGACGAGUGUGGGAAGACAUUCACCCGGAGGCCCAACCUCAUGAAGCACCAGAGGAUUCACACUGGGGAGAAACCCUACAAGUGUGGGGAGUGUGGGAAGCACUUUAGCGCCUACUCUUCCCUGAUUUAUCACCAGAGAAUCCACACCGGAGAGAAACCCUAUAAAUGUAAUGACUGCGGGAAAGCCUUCAGUGAUGGCUCAAUCCUUAUCCGACAUCGUCGGACUCACACCGGAGAGAAGCCAUUUGAGUGCAAGGAAUGUGGCAAAGGCUUUACACAAAGUUCUAACCUUAUCCAACAUCAGAGAAUUCACACUGGAGAGAAACCCUAUAAAUGUAAUGAAUGUGAGAAAGCUUUCAUUCAAAAAACCAAACUCGUGGAACAUCAGAGAAGCCACACUGGAGAGAAGCCCUAUGAAUGCAAUGACUGUGGCAAAGUUUUCAGCCAAAGCACACACCUCAUCCAGCACCAGAGAAUCCACACAGGAGAGAAGCCCUACAAGUGCAGCGAGUGUGGGAAGGCCUUCCACAACAGUUCCAGACUCAUCCACCACCAGAGGCUGCACCACGGAGAGAAACCCUACAGAUGCAGCGAUUGCAAGAAAGCCUUCAGCCAGAGCACGUACUUGAUUCAGCACCGGAGGAUCCACACCGGGGAGAAGCCCUACAAGUGCAGCGAGUGUGGGAAGGCCUUCCGGCACAGUUCCAACAUGUGUCAGCAUCAGCGGAUUCACCUCCGGGAGGACUUCUCCAUGUAACAGUGGCGCGGUGUCCGAGGGCAGAGUCCAGCUGAGCACUUCCUGCAUGCGCCCCCGGCACCUGACUCUGCCCUUUAUGUAUUAUCCACACGAUGUUUUCACAGAGUGAAAGGACGUUUCUCAUUAAACAAACCUCUUUUCUUAAAUCAAAAGCAGUGCAUGUUCAUUUUAGAGAAAUUGAGACAGAAAAGUGGGCAAAAAAGAAGCUUCUGUGAUCUCUCCCACUUAGAAAAAAAAUUCAUUGCUGCUGAUUUACGAAUAUUUUCGAGACAUACUGGAGAGCAUUUUAAAAAGAAAAUACCGUAAUGCUUGUCAUUGCAGCACCUAGGAUCUUCACUUUUGCUAUUUCCUCAAUAUCAGAAAAUUCACACUGAAGAGAGCACCAUAUAUUUUAACAUUUUUACAUAUUGUAAAUUUAAAAGCAUCGGCCAGGUGUGGUGGCUCAUGCCUGUAAUACCAGCAUUUUGAGAGGCCAAGGUGGGUGGAUCACUUGAGGUCAGGAGUUUGAGACCAGCCUGGCCAACAUGGUGAAACCCCGUCUCUACUAAAAAUACAAAAAUUAGCCAGGUGUGGUGGUGGGUGCCUGUAAUCCCAGCUACUCGGGAGGCUGAGGCAGGAGCAUUGCUUGAACCUGGGAGGCGGAGGUUGCAGUGAGCCAAGACUGUGCCACUGUACUCCAGCCUGGGUGACAGAGCGAGACGCUGUCUCAAAAAAUAAAUGAAACAAACUUAACAUUCAUACUUUUUAUGUCAAUAGAGUUGAAGUUGCCUUUAACUGUGGUGAAAUAACAUAAUAUGAAAUUUACAAUUUUAACCAUUUUUAAGUGUACAAUUCAGUGGCAUUAAGUACAUUCAUGGUGUUGUGUAACCAUCAUCACUGUGUAUUUCCAGAACUGUUUUAUUACUCCAAACAGAAACCCUGUACCUAUUAAAUAAUAACUCUUCAUUUCCCCCUUCUCCCUACUGCUGGUAACCUCAAUUCUAUUUUCUGUCUCUUUGAAUUUGCCUAUUCUAGGAACAUAAAUAUGUGUGGAAUCAUGCAA